CCAUGCUGUCCGGAUGGUGCCUGUGAUUACAGAGGAAAUACCUUUCAACUGGAAGAUAUCAUUAAACACAGGAAAAGAGAUCAGUACAUCGAGAAAUUAACAAAGGAGAGGGAUGCUCCGAGUCUGGAACUGUACAGGAACACCAUAACCGAUGAGGAGUUGAAGGAGAAAAAUGCUGAACUACAAGAAAAACUUCGACUUGUAGAAUCUGAAAAGUCUGAGAUCCAGCUCAACGUAAAGGACCUUAAAAGGAAGCUGGAAAGGGCCCAGCUCCUGCUGCCACAGCAGCAGCUGCAGGUGGAGGCUGACCGCCUGGGUAAGGAGCUACAGAGUGUGUCAGCAAAGCUCCAAGCCCAGGUGGAAGAGAACGAGUUGUGGAACCUCCUGAACCAGCAACAAGAGGAGAAGAUGUGGAGGCAGGAGGAGAAGAUACAGGAGCAGGAAGAGAAGAUGUGUGAGCAGGAGCUGAAGAUAAGGGAGCAGGAGGAGAAGAUGUGGAGGCAGGAGGAGAAGAUGCAUGAGCAGGAAGAGAAGAUACGGGAGCAGGAGGACAAGAUGUGGAGGCAGGAGGAGAAGAUACGGGAGCAGGAAGAGAAGAUACGGGAGCAGGAGGAGAAGAUGUGGAGGCAGGAGGAGAAGAUACGGGAGCAGGAUGAGAAGAUACAGGAGCAGGAGGAGGAGAUGUGGAGGCAGGAGGAGAAGAUACGGGAGCAGGAGGAGAAGAGGCAGGAGAAGAUGUGGAGGCAGGAGAAGAAGAUGCGCGAGCAGGAUGAGAAGAUACGGGAGCAGGAGGAGGAGAUGUGGAGGCAGGAGGAGAAGAUACGGGAGCUGGAGGAGAUGAUGCAAGAUCAGGAGGAGAAGCUGCGGGAGGUGGAGGAGAAAAUGCAGGAGGAGGAGGAAAAGAUGCAGGAGCAGGAGGAGAAGAUACAGAGGCAGGAGGAGAAGAUCCAGGAGCAGGAGGAGAAGACGUGGAGGCAGGAGAAGCUGCUCAAGCAGGAAGAGAAGAUAUGGGAGCAGGAGGAGAAGAUGUGGAGGCAGGAGGAGAAGAUGUGGGAACAGGAGGAGAAGAUGCAGGAACAGGAGGAGAAGAUGCAGAGGCAGGAGGAGAAGAUGCGGGAGCAGGAAGUGAGGCUGUGGCAGCAGGAGGAGAAGAUGCAGGAACAGGAGGAGCACCUGGAAGCUGCCAUCUACCAAGCAGAUGACAAGAACACAAAUAUAAUAAACAUGUAAAAGCCGGCAGCAAGGCCUGGAGAAGAGUAAGCUGCCAUGUGACUGUUUAGAAUAGAGUCUGAGCACAAACCUGAAAAAAAAAAAAAGAAAAUUUAUUUAUUUUAAAUUUUGGCAAAAUACUGGCCAGGCACGGUGGCUCAUGCCUGUAAUCCCAGCAAUUUGGGAGGCUGAGGUGAAUGGAUGACCUGAGGUCAGGAGUUCAAGGCCAGCCUGGCCAAUACAAAAAUUAGCCGGGCAUGGUGGCACAUGCCUGUAAUCCCAACUACUUGGGAGGCUGAGGCAGGAGAAUCGCUUGAACCUGGGAGGCAGAGGUUGCAGUGAGCUGAGAUCGUGCCACUGCACUCAAGCCUGGGUGACAGAGUGAGACUCUGUCUCAAAAAAAAAAAAAAAGUUUCUUCCUUACAUGUAUGUUUCUAUUAGUUUUUUUCUUGGUCUUUCUCAUUUAGUCUGAUGUUGUCUUAUGGCAUUCCUAGUAAAGUUUUAUCUGCCUCCA